GCAGUCAGCGAGCCCACGUGCUUGUGUUGACUGGACAACUUCCUGGUGGAAAACCGCGACUCUUGCAAGUGGGCAAACUUGACGUUUUCGCUAUGGGCAAACGCGGGAGCCGGAGCCAGAGCCAGCUACUCAACACCCUAACUAAAAAGCAGAAGAAACAUCUUCGAGAUUUCGGCGAGGAGCAUCCCUUCUAUGACAGGGUUUCCAGAAAGGAAGCAAAGCCACAGAUUUGUCAACUGUCAGAGAGUUCAGAUUCUUCAGAUUCUGAAAGCGACUCAGAGAGUGAACCACAACAAGUUUCUGGCUACCACAGACUACUUGCUACAUUAAAGAAUGUUUCUGAGGAAGAAGAGGAAGAUGAGGAGGAGGAAGAGGAAGAAGACAGUAUUGUAGAUGAUGCAGAAAUGAACGAUGAAGAUGGUGGUAGCGAUGUCAGUGUGGAAGAAGAGAUGGCUGCAGAGUCUACUGAAAGUCCAGAGAAUGUAGCUUUAUCUGCUGACCCUGAGGGAAAAGAAGAUGGGGAAGAGCCACCGGGCACAUCACAAACAUCCCCCGAAGAGUUCACAGAUGCAAAACACGAGUCACUGUUCAGCCUGGAAACCAAUUUUCUGGAAGAGGAAAGUGGAGACAACUCUUCUUUGAAAGCCUCUCAAGAUCCAUUUCUUCAACAUGUGAACAAAGAACUGAAAGAAAAAGCAAUUCAGGCUGUUGCCACAAAUCCCAAAACUACCCACGAGCUUAAAUGGCCUAUUCUGGGCCAGCUUUUCUUUUCCUCUAAGUUUCAGAAGUUGGAAACAUUUAAACCCCCAAAGGAUAUUGACUUAAAGUCACUUCAUCUCCAGAAGCCUCUGGAAUCCACCUGGACUAAGACCAACAGCCAGUUCCUAUCUGGUCCCCAAAAAUCAAGCAGCCCAUUCACCCCCCUCCAGAAAGAACUCUUCUUAAUUAUGAAUUCUUACCGGGACCUGUUCUACCCGGAAAGGACUGCUCUGAAGAACGGGGAAGAGAUCCGCCAUGUGUAUUGCCUGCAUGUGAUAAAUCACAUCCUCAAAGCCAAUGCCCAGGUGCUUGGCAACAAUAGCAGACGCCGAAGCCAGAAGUUUGGAGUGGGUGAUGAUGAUGACUUCAGAGACCAAGGGUUAACAAGGCCCAAGGUACUGAUAGUGGUGCCAUUCCGGGAAGCUGCUUUGCGGGUGGUGCAGCUCUUCAUCAGCCUCCUCGAGGGUGACAGCAAGAAGAAAAUCAUUGUGAGCAACAAAAAGAGGUUUCAGGGAGAAUAUGGAUCAGAUCCCGAGGAGAGACCACCCAACUUGAAGAGGCCUGAGGAUUAUGAAGCCGUAUUUGUGGGCAAUAUUGAUGACCACUUCAGGAUUGGAGUGGCAAUACUUCAGAGAAGCAUCCGACUCUAUGCCCCGUUUUACUCCUCGGAUAUCCUCAUUGCUUCCCCCCUGGGCUUGAGGACCAUCAUUGGUGGAGAAGGAGAGAAGAAGAGAGAUUUUGACUUUCUGUCUUCUAUCGAGCUUCUCAUCAUUGAUCAAGCUGACAUUUACCUGAUGCAGAACUGGGAGCAUGUCCUGCAUUUGAUGAAUCACAUGAACCUACUACCCCUGGACUCACAUGGGGUAGACUUUUCUCGAGUGCGGAUGUGGAGCCUCAAUAAUUGGUCCAAGUACUAUCGCCAGACACUGCUAUUUGGGGCCCUUCAGGAUGCCCAGAUCAACUCAGUGUUCAACAAGUACUGUGUCAACAUGCAAGGCCAGGUGGCCGUGAGGAAUGUCCCAAUGACAGGCUCUAUCAGUCAUGUCCUGGUGCAGCUCCCACAUGUCUUCCAGAGGAUGGAAGCUGAAAACCUAGCUUCAGUGAUUGAUGCCAGGUUUAACUUUUUUGUGAACAAGAUUUUGCCACAGUAUCGUGAUGCAGUCAUGUCUCACACGCUCAUCUAUAUCCCCUCCUACUUUGACUUCGUGCGUCUUCGAAAUUACUUCAAGAAGGAGGAAUUGAAUUUUACCCACAUCUGCGAGUACACGCAGAAGUCUGGUGUCUCCAGGGCCAGACACUUCUUCCUUCAAGGAGAGAAACAGUUUCUACUUUUCACAGAGCGCUUCCAUUUCUACAAAAGGUAUACAAUAAAAGGCAUCAGGAACCUGAUUUUCUAUGAACUGCCGACAUAUCCACACUUUUACAGUGAAAUCUGUAAUAUGCUGAGAGCCACCAACAGAGGAGAAGAGGCCACGUGGACCUGCACUGUUCUCUACUCCAAAUAUGAUGCCCAGAGGUUAGCUGCCGUGGUUGGUGUGGAGCGGGCGGCACAGAUGCUACAGUCCAACAAGAAUGUCCACCUCUUCAUUACUGGAGAAAAAUGAAAUUUUGUUGGGCAGGAAGUGGUAUUUGGCAUGAUACAUAAUGUUUGAUUCUAUGCCAUUUGGACCCAAUUCUGAUUACUUACAGAAGAAGGACUGAUACAAAGAAAGUGCAUGAGGCAAUGUCAGUAUUAUCUGACAUCUUUCUUUUCAGGUCAUGUGUCCCUGAAAAGUUAAAUGUAAACCAGAUUUUGGUAAAUCCCAUCUUUCAGAAGUGAAGAGGGGGCUAGAAGGACUCUGAGAAGUUGGUAGAAGAAAACUCCCACUUGUGAAUAUUUUUGUGAGACAUAAAUUCUUUUAUUACGAUUUACCUCUAAUUUAUUACACUUAGUAAAUUCUUCCAGAUUUUUCUAUUUGUUUGACACUUCCUUAAAGUAAGGAAUACACAUUGCUUGCGAGAACUGGUUAUGAGACAUUGGAAUACUUCUUGCUGCUACAUGUCAUCUUAAUUUUGGAUGGCAUGGGUUUUGUAAAACUUAUUCUGCCCCAGCCAAACUUUUUUGAAACCUUAAAUAGUCUACCUUAAUUCAGCCUAGAAGAGUACAUUGAUUUACUGAUCUUUUUUCAUAUUCAUAAUACUAAAUGUUUUAGUUUUGUUCAAAUAUAUGCUUAAAAUCACGUUAUUUAAAAAACACAUCAGCUCUGUCUCAAGAAGUAAUUUUGUUGAAACUCCAUGUUAAAAUAUCCAUCUUCAACAGUAGUGUCUUCAUAAUAACUAGUCAUUUUUUCAGUCAUAAACAGAUGCAAAUAAAAAGGAAAUUACACUUUUAAAAACAUUUUUAUUUUGAAACAUUCUCAAACAGAAAAAUUCCAAGUACAGAACCUGAACCAUUUGAGAGUGAGUUGCCAACCCAGUGGGCCUAUCACCUUUAAAUACUUUAGUAUAUAUUUCCUGUAAACAAUUAAGGGUAUUGUUUGUGAUUAGGAAUGCCCCACCAAUAAGGAUAAUGUGAAUAUUUCAGAAUCCAAAAAAAUUCGAAACACGUCUGGUCCCAAGCAUUUCAGAUAAGAGAUAUUCAACUCAUCCUAGUAUGGACUCGUAGUUUCUUCUUUUAUUCAAUGGGUUACGGUUUGUUACAUCAUUAUUUCUUUAGAUGCGUAACUGGUCUCAAAUAUGGCCGCUGGGAGCACCUUCAGGUUAGCCCCUGUGUACUUUUGACAUGUCCCCCAUCUACUUGGGCACUGCUGUAUUUUUUGACAAUGAGACAUUCCAGGUUUCUCUACUCCAGCCCUGCUUGCUUUUAGUAGGAAAUUAUUAUAAAAGGUUAGAUUGGAGUGCUUACUAUUGUGGUGCCACUCAUCCCAGGCUCAGUGGUCAGAACUUGGGAAUUGUGUACAUGUAUGCACACACAUAUGUACACACGUUGUCUAAAUUUGCUUCACAUUAAUAUCUAAAUUUACUUUCAUAUCCAUAUAUUGAAAACCAUGAAUUCACACCAGUACCUCCAAUUCUAGUCCAACAACACAGGAUUGCUUCUCAUUUUCUUUCCAUAUUGAUAACUCCUUUCUCAGACAGUGGCUCCCAUUAUCCUCAAUGUAAUAACCCAUGAUUGGUACAGAUUUUUUUUAUCCUUGGGCACGCUUAAAAUUACUUAGCAAAAACAAAAAGUAAAAUCAGUUUUGAAGUAAUAUUUCUGCUAAAUAUUUAGACAUUUUUACUUCUUUUUCUUCAGCAUGGUAAGUAAAACCAUUUAUUCCAUAUUUAGAUGGUUUUCUAAAUUUCAGAAAAUUUAGUUAGAUAAAAGCCGACCGAACCCAUGCUACAAAGAACUUUUUGUAUCUAUAGGCAUGCCCUGUGGUUACUGGCGUAAUUGUGCUGCUGUUUAUCAUAGAUCCUGUAUAUUAUGAGAAUAAGAAAUGAGUUUAUUUACCUCAUUCAGAAAUGUGAGGCGAAGGGACUGUAAUUACCUGGAUCUUUUUUUUUUUUUUUGAGAUGGAGUCUCGCUCUGUUGCCCAGGCUGGAGUACACUGGCAUGAUCUUGGCUUACUGCAAUCUGUGCCUCCCGAGUUCAAGCGAUUCUCGUGCCUCCGCCUCCCAAGUAGCUGGGACUACAGGCGCAUGCCACCAUGCACAGCUAAUUUUUUAUAUUUUUAGUAGAGAUGGGGUUUUGCCAUGUUGGCCAGGCUGGUCUCAAACUCUUGACCUCAAGUGAUCUGCCCACCUCAGCCUCCCAAAGUGCUGGGGUUACAGGCCUGAGCCGCCACGCCUGGCCAAUUACCUACAUCUUUUUCUACUGCCAUAUUCUUUUGCCUGUGAAUUGUAGUUCAUCUCGUGGUUUCCAUUAUUACUAUUCACACGACUCCCAAAUCUCCAGCUUCUCUGGCUCUCCACUCACAUGUGAGUCUGGAUUUCAAAUCCAUGAUGUAGCCCCAGAAAUAACCAUUUUAUUAAGCACCCCUAGUGAUUUUCAUGCUGGCAUAGAGCCAAACCCAGCCAACUGCUUCUUGCCUGCAGAGAACACUGAGGAUUUCAAGUGUGAACAAAGUAGUGUUGCUUUGUUCCUGGCUCAGCACCUGAAAAGAAGGUAAGCCUCUGCAGUUAGCCCUGGCUCCUUAGUGCAUUGCAGAGUGGAGUCUCUGCAAUGGUUUUAUUAAAAGGAUGCCUUGAAGAUCUGGUCUCUCUCAACACACAAUAAGCGAGAAGAGAGGCUACUGAAAUACGGAUGCGUGAGCUGGAAUUACACACUACCUUGAUGUUAACAAGGCUCAUUUGCAGCAAGCAAGUGCCUAUAUAGGGUCUGAAAUAUAGACAAAGGAUGGUCCCAAUCCUGGAAACAGUGGAAUUAAAAGGUAUGGAAAGGAACUUACCCAGAAAGUAACACUUUUAAAUGUUUUUUCUUUUCCCAUAGUUAAAACAACCAGCUUAGCACUUUUCUUUUUGAGAGAGAAAAAGCUUUGAAUCGUGGAUGCUUCUCACAGCUGGCUGCACCACGUGCAGUGUUCAAAAAACAAGAACAAGCUAAUCAUAGAGAACCAGCAGCAGCUAAACAGCCCUCUGCUUGCUUCCAAAGGGCUUAUAAUUGAGCACAGAUGGUCCUAGUGGAGAUGGGGAAUGUGUCCCUGCUGACUCCUCAUACCCCAGAGGACCAAGGGGGGCUCAUGAAGGCUCUCAGCCCUGAUUGUGCCCUCGUGAGGGCAAGGAGCUAUGCUGCUGAAGGAGGAAAGGGAAAGGCAGGUGGGGCCAGACCCUAUUGGCCAUCUGACCAGCCUUCCCAAGCCCACGUGAGCAGAUCUAGGGUCUCAAGAUUACAGAAGGCCUGGGGUGAGGGAGCAAGAGUUGGAAGUUCUUUAUAGUUGUCUGAAGAGCCUCAUUGUCCAACUGCAGGGGCCUGAGGUGCCCAAAGCUUCGUGGAAAAGUAAUGUCAGUGGAAUGCUCAGAAGUGGCUCUUUUCAGGGCACGGCUUCUGAGGAGCGUGGGGCCACCACAGCUAGCCCUCCCUCCGUCUAGCCAUCCUCUCCUUCCAGUCCCUUUCCCAUCUUUUCUCUCAAAGGAGCAUGGUAGUGAUCUUCAUUACCAAAUUUCUACUCCACACUUAUUUUAAAAAGCUUUUCUGAAAGCCUGGCUACAUAGAAUUCUAAACAGAUUUCAGUCAACUUUUAAUUAGAGUCAAUGAAUGGGGAGUAAAUACACAGAUAAUCCAAAAUUGAUGUAAGCAUUGGAAGGGGAAAGAGGGAACGCUUCUUUCCCUCUGGGCUUGGUCAUUUCCUCCCAAGCAAACCCCGCGACGUUCAGCCGUCUUCCUCCUAUGCCACGUGCUCUCACCAGAACUGCAGCAAAACUGCAUUUUAUGUCCUGUGUCUAAAGCUAAACACAUGUUCCUGUCUACUUUUGCUUUGUUCCUGUUUCCCUUCUGUGAGGACCUUCCCCUCCUCAGAUGUGGGGAGUUGCCGCCUCCACUUGCAUUACAUGUAUUUCAGAGUAGGUCCUAGGCUCCCCUUACACCUCUGGUCACGUUGCCAUUAUUCCUAUGGUAGAUAAAGGGGAUGAGAAAGAACAGAGCUCCAGGCCUUUUUCAAACAAACUGGUUUUCUCAGUAUAGCCCUAUGCUCAAAAGGAGUGAGGACAGGUAUGUGACUGCCAUAAGGAGCUGUUUGCUUUGCACAGAGAAAUCUAAUCUUUCUCCUGCUGGGCAGCUCAGUACAGAUGUCCCCUCACUGCUGGAAGAAACACCUGCCCUUGCUUGUUCUCCUGAUGGCCCCUCACAGUCAGGUGUGGGAUGGCACAUUUCUAGGUGCUCCUCGCCGAGCUGUCAUGGGCUUCAGUCUUGGGCCUCUGCAGCUGGCUGUGACCAGGUGGAAACUGUAGCCUUGGCUGACCCAGAGAAGGAAAGGAGGCAGUCUGCCGCUUGGCUGAUUUAGGAGUUGUGCUGAAUUCCUGCCCAUCUGUUCUCCCAGCUGAGCCAAGGCCAAAGCUGUCUACCUUUUGCCAACCUAAGGAAUGACACAGAGCAUGGAGCACCAUCACUGAAACAUCUGCCCCAGUGCCCUGCCACCUUCGUCCUCACUGACCUCUGCAGCCUCUCUCAUCUGCCAGUUUUGAUUCCGCAAGGAGAGGUGGCCCUGGGCUCACAGCUGGUGUUUGUCCACAGAUGUUCAUGGGUUUCUUUGUGUUCUCUCAUUUUUUCAAAGCUGGGUGUUGGGACCAACAUCACCACUGACAUUCUGUGGCUCUAAACAAGUCCUCACGACCACUUCUCAGUUUUCUCAUCUUUAUGAAGUAUGGAGUAAUCCCCACUAGCCUUAUAGAGGGACUGUGUGAGAAGGGAAGAGACUGCUAUUGUUUGCCCUAUAUCCACCUACUUCCCUAGUUCCAGAACGCUGGACUUUAAUGAGAUAACAAAGUACCUAGUAAAAACACUGCAUCAUUUUCCAUCCCCCACCCCUUGCAGUAAAAUGUGGCCCAUGAGACAGAAGCACUAACUACUGAGCAGGACUUCUAGGGGAGUUCUUUAAAACUCAGAGGAGCACCACUUUUACCUUCUGCUCUUCCCUUUUUCCUGCCUGGAACGCAGAAGUGAUGGCUGAAGCUCCUGAGGCUAUAAGCUCUGUACGUAGGAGAGUGGUGAAGAAAGGAGCUUGGUUCUGCAAGGAUGUUGUAGAGCUGCCAUACCAGUCCUGCAUGGUAUUCCUGUGCACUACUGUUACGUGAACACACAAACACCUAAUUUGUUUAAGCCAUUAGGCCAGGCCUCUAUUAGCCAUUCCUGACUGAUACAGAAGACAAAAAUGGCAUCACAGACUCCUGAACUCCAAAGACACUGCCUAUUCUUUCGUCUGUUCUUGGCAAGCACCAACAUUGAGACUGUACUUCAGGGUUGAUGCUGGCCAUUUGGUGGCGUGAGGAGUGGGCACUCACAUGUCUCUGCUAGCAGUUCUGACGUGUCCAUUCCACACUGGAUCCAUAGAACGAGGGAACACAAGUGUCUUCUCAUAAGAUUUAUAGAAACAGUGAUCGUUGCAGAAAAAUAAUUAGCAAGAGAACAGACUUCAGCUCUCUGAAGGCUGAUGACCACCUGUUUCUCAUCUCUUCUAGUGUAUGUCAAAGCUAAAUUAGGUCAAAUAGGAAAUAAGUCAGAAUCCCCAAUUCGAUAGAAACUUACAGGUCUUGUGAUCUAAUCUGCCACUUGAUCCGUGAAUUACCUAUAGGUCAUCCCUAAGAGGUGGCCUCCAGCUUCUGCUUGAAUUCCUUCAAGGAUGGGGUGCUCAUUGUGGCUUUUCUAAUCAUCUCUGAUUGUUAGAAACACUGUGAAACUUUUAUCCAUCAGUCCUGUUUCUGAAGCUGUACGGUACAAAUUUUUUUUUUCCCCACUUAAGGCUCAACUAUUGGAAUACAUCUACCAUGUCUCCUAUGAAACUUGCUUCUCCAGGCCAAUCAUCCUUACUUCCUUAAACUUUUUUUUUUCCUGAAAAGUUAUUCUUUUAAUCUUAUUAAAAAAGCAACCCAUGCCCAUUCCACAAAUACAAGUGAAAUAGUGAAAAACAAAAAUCAAACUACAUCUAUUUGGUGAUCAUUAUUAAUGUCUUAUGUUUCCUCCCAGAUUGUUUUCUGCAUGAAUAAUAACCAACAAUGUGUGUGUAUGUAUAUAUAUGCUUUUGCAUUAAAAGGUGGUUUUGAAGGUAA